CGAGGGGAUGGCAGGAGAUCAAUCGGACCCAGAACAGAGGCCUGCAAGGAUGAGCGCACUUGAUCCCCUCAGAGAAAAAGCCAGAGUGACUCACAGGAGAAAGACAAAGCAACCAAAGCUUCCAGGGUGUACAGGAGGUCCAAAGUCACCAGAAGGAAGAAGAAAACCUGAAACAGCGAGAGCUGGCCAAACGCUGCUAAGACCUAUGCAAAUAAGACCCACCCACGCUACCUGGAAAUCGGGCCUGGGAAGUCAGAAAACAAAGCACAUGCGUGCAGGGCUGCACGAACGGAGGCGGAGGAGGCGGCUCCGAGGGAGCAGCUGAUCCUGAAACAGCAGUGGAUCCCUGGGAGAGCAGCACAGAUAAAGAUCCAGGCAAUAAUGAUGCUUCCUCCUCUUGGACAGCCUUUUACAGUUCUGGCCAUGGAACUUCAGAGAAGGUAGGUCUGAUUUGGGGGGAAACAGGAGAUCUUGACGUGUAGUAAUACAAGCUUACUGGAUGGAGUAAAGUUAGAAUUUUCAGGUAAGAGAAUUAAAAAAAAAAAAAAAACUUAUAAUCUUGCCCCCAGAGAUAACCACUGCUAAUAUCUGGUUGUUUAUCUCUCCAGACAUUUUUUCCAUUGCACACACACUUUUGGAAAUUGGAUUAUAUGGUAAUAUGGUUUUGUUGCUGGUUCUUUUUCGCUUAAUGACAUUAUAUCCUAGGUAUAUAUCCAUAUUAAUAGUUUUACCACAUCAUAUUAAAGGCUGCAUAAUAUCUCUUCCUAUGGAUGGAGCAGAAUCUACUUAAUCAAUGUCCUAUUACUGGAUGAUGACGUAGUUCUCCAUACGUCACCGUUAAACCAGCGCCUGGAUGGGCAUCUCUUUACUCACAUCUUUGCAGAAGUCCUUGAUGGUUUCCGUGGAAUCGAUUCCCAGUGGGGGAAAUGAUGAGUCAAGGUUACAUACAGUUUACGGCCUCUGGUAAGUAUUAAAGAUCUGCUUCUAACACACUCUGGGAUUCAGGGGCUUCUCAAAGCUUGAUGCAGAGGACUUUGUCACGGCUUUGAAAUCAACCUUGACCCUUCCUUUCUCUCAAAUCCAUUUGCAUUAAUAAUUUCAACUGCCUCAUAUAUCCAUAACAAUGUUUUGAUCAACAGUGAAUUACAUAUGUGAUGGUGGCCACCUAAGAUUAUAAUACCAUAUAUUUACCUUGCCUUUUCUAAGUUUAUGUUGAAAGACACACGCAAUUAUCAUUGUGUUACAAUUGCCUACAGUGUUCAGAACAUAAUAAGCUGUAUGGGUUUGUAGCCUAGGAGCAACAGGCUAGACCGUAUAGCCUAGGCAUGUAGCAGGCUCUACCAUCUAGGUUUGUGUAAAUACUCUCUGUGCUGUUCAUACAACGAUGUGUUUCUGAGAACAUAGUCCCAUUUUUAGGUCAUGCAUUGCUUUGUGGUCUUUACUGGGUGCUGGGCUCUAACUAAAAGCUUUACUAGUUUUGGCUUCCUUUGCACAAGGAGAAAUAGAGGCACAGAGAGGUCAAGCAAUUCAACUGGAAUCACAGCCCUAAAUAGCCAUGGAUCUGGCAUCAUGAACCUUGACAGAAACUACAACUGGAUCCCUAGAACUCCACUGCUUCUUGGGAAGUGGCUUUGAUUCUGUCCCCAAAGAUAUCACUUAUCCCAUCCCCUUUUAUCUCCUCUGCCACUGCCUAACCUGCACCACCAUCACACGCCUGAGCCACACUGCUGCAGCCCGAACGGGUGUUCCCUUCCCGAUCUUAUCCCUCUCAGCCUGUCCUCUGCUCUGCAGCUAGAAUGGUGUUUUAAAAAUGGAAAUAGGAUCAGGUACCUUACCCUACCGCUCACCCCUGGAAUAAAAUCCAGAUGAGCUCCUGAGUUCACAGGUCCCGAGUACUAUACCCUCCCACCUUGCCUACUCCGGUCACCACACCUUGAUCACCCUGGGCUCCUUUCACUUUCUCAAAUUGGAAGAGCUUUUCUCACCUCGGGGCCACACAUGCUGUUCCCUGGGCCUGCAACGCUCUUCCUCCACUGUGCGUGGCUGGAUUCCUAUAUACUUUGGUCUCAGCUCUUCUGUCAUCUCUUUGCAGAAACCUUCUCUGGUGGUCUCAUUGGGAGCAGCCACCAAGCACCCGAAGCCCAUUUUCCUUUUUGCCCUUUAUUAACAACCAUUAAAAUUGUGUAUUUAUUUAUUGCCCAUUAUUCAUUAAAUGUCUUUUUGCCUCACUACACUCUAAAUGUCAUGAGGUCAAAGACAAUGUCUAUUUUGUUCACCAUAAUACCUUGCACAGCACCUGGGCUAGAGUAAGCACUCAAUAAUGUCCGAGUGGAUGAAUGGACUGCAGAAUAAAGCACUGGUGCAGAGCCCUGCUAAACUACCCUAGUUUCGCUUAGGGCUCCAUCUCCCUCUGCAUAUCUUCAUUUCCUCCUUCCCUGUUUGGAGCAGUGCCAGAGGUCUAGAAGAAAACCAGGAAGCCACAGGUCCGAGAGUAUAAGCAGGUUUUGCUUCAGACAUCGGCUCAGUCGGGGUAGAUGAUGUCAUAUCAGGGGCUCUAGGGAGACUCCCUUCCCCCAGAUCCCCUCUUCCACAGUUCCUGGAUUUCUACCAUGAGUCUUCUGGCCGUGAAGGAUUCCUGAUCACAUGCAAACACUUAUUAUCUAGCUAGUAACACGCACUGAGUAGGGGGACGGCAUGGAUGCAGCCUUCUGUCUUUACGAAAACCAUGAGUCUGAAGACAUGGGUCCCAUGUCACCAUUAACUAGCUGGGUGACUUUGGAUCAACUCUUCAAAUUAUUCGAAUGACCCAUAUGAGAAACAGAGAAAAGCCAAGUAUUUCUGGUUGAAACGGAGAAGCUGGGCUGGAGUGCGCCUCCCUCCAACUCCCCGCUUUAACUCCCUAAGGUUGGUGGGAUGGCCAGCUCUAAGAUCUCAGAAGGCUGACCAGCUGUGUGCUAAGAACAAAGCAGAAGGCAGCGAGGUUUGUACACGCUGAUUGCAGUUACUUAGGCACAUUAAAAGAUCAGCGGGUGACUGGACUGAAUCUGAUAGUCGGAGCUCUUAAGCUUCGAAGUAGGUGACUUUCACAGCAACCAAAGUGCUGAGCAGGCAGCCCCUUUGUGCAAGGAGGAGGUUCCAGCCACUUUCGAAGAGAAAUGAGGGCCCCAGAGAGAGGAAGCCCAGAAGACUCAGUUACCCUCUUCACAUCUACAAAGACGAAAUUGCCACCCUACCUUUCCAGACCAGGGACUCCAGGUGUUGAAGGGACUGCCCACAAUCUCACAGGUGCUUGGCUUCCAGGUUCAAUUAGUUGCCAUGCCCUGGGGGGAACUCAGGUCCCCCAUCUUCCUCCCCACCCCACCCCCCAGGAAGCUCUCUGGCCUUGGCUCCAAGCAGGUGUGCUCAAGAGGCUGCCGACUGGGCCACCUGGCAGCCCCAGGUGCUGCGUGCAUGCUGCCAUGGAGACAGGCCCCUGGGUUGGUGGCAAGAAGGCAGUCUCCCAAAGCUUUGCCGAUUCAGGGGAGGGAGCAACUGGAGCCUCAGGCCCUCCAGAGUAGUCUGCCUGACCACCCUGGAGCCCACAGAAGCCCAGGACGUCUCCCGCGAAGCCUCCCCGUGUGUGGCUGAGGAUGGCUGAGCAGCAGGGCCGGGAGCUUGAGGCUGAGUGCCCCGUCUGCUGGAACCCCUUCAACAACACGUUCCAUACCCCCAAAAUGCUGGAUUGCUGCCACUCCUUCUGCGUGGAAUGUCUGGCCCACCUCAGCCUUGUGACUCCAGCCCGGCGCCGCCUGCUGUGCCCACUCUGUCGCCAGCCCACAGUGCUGGCCUCAGGGCAGCCUGUCACUGACUUGCCCACGGACACUGCCAUGCUCGCCCUGCUCCGCCUGGAGCCCCACCAUGUCAUCCUGGAAGGCCAUCAGCUGUGCCUCAAGGACCAGCCCAAGAGCCGCUACUUCCUGCGCCAGCCUCAAGUCUACACGCUGGACCUUGGCCCCCAGCCUGGGGGCCAGACUGGGCCGCCCCCAGACACGGCCUCUGCCACCGUGUCUACGCCCAUCCUCAUCCCCAGCCACCACUCUUUGAGGGAGUGUUUCCGCAACCCUCAGUUCCGCAUCUUUGCCUACCUGAUGGCCGUCAUCCUCAGUGUCACUCUGUUGCUCAUAUUCUCCAUCUUUUGGACCAAGCAGUUCCUUUGGGGUGUGGGGUGAGUGCUGUUCCCAGACAAGAAACCAAACCUUUUUCGGUUGCUGCUGGGUAUGGUGACUACGGAGCCUCAUUUGGUAUUGUCUUCCUUUGUAGUGUUGUUUAUUUUACAAUCCAGGGAUUGUUCAGGCCAUGUGUUUGCUUCUGGGAACAAUUUUAAAAAAAAACAAAAAAACGAAAAGCUUGAAGGACUGGGAGAUGUGGAGCGACCUCCGGGUGUGAGUGUGGCGUCAUGGAAGGGCAGAGAAGCGGUUCUGACCACAGAGCUCCACAGCAAGUUGUGCCAAAGGGCUGCACAGUGGUAUCCAGGAACCUGACUAGCCCAAAUAGCAAGUUGCAUUUCUCACUGGAGCUGCUUCAAAAUCAGUGCAUAUUUUUUUGAGUUGCUCUUUUACUAUGGGUUGCUAAAAAAAAAAAAAAAAUUGGGAAGUGAGCUUCAAUUCUGUGGGUAAAUGUGUGUUUGUUUCUCUUUGAAUGUCUUGCCACUGGUUGCAGUAAAAGUGUUCUGUAUUCAUUAA